AGUGUUUCAGAAUGAGACCAAAGCGGUGACAUUUUCAACCUCUUCGGUCUCUCUUCAGUUUUUUCAUUUUAAGUUUUUGUUGUGCUUCUAUCACUUAAAGGAAGCCUCCAAGUUGAAAUCAAAUACUAAUGACAUUUUUAUCUAAUGUAUAAAUGUGUUUUUAUUAUUUAUUAGGAAAUUUAUUUUACUUGGCCCUCAGCCAUGACAUAUCAUGGCAUAAUCACUAUCCUAAAUUUGUAUAUCUUAUCCUUGCAUAAGGUAAGACUUUCUAUGAAUUACACAUAUUUGUAUUUUCCUCUCUUACAUAUUUUAAGAAUUUUUUUAUACUUUGUUUUCUGCAAAUGAAAUAUUGCUCAUAAGCCAGGUGAUGGCUGUCCACGCCUCUUUUCCCCUGCUUACCCUUGCUUAGAUCUUAUGGUAGAAUCUUUUCAUAGAAGACACAGAAAGACAUGAAAGAAAGAGCUGGAGAAGCCUGAGGGGCUGCCCAGUGAGUGGUCUGCUAGGAUGCUGUGCCACAGCCCAGGCACAGGAGGCAGGGAGAGCAAUGGGGCCCUUCCCUUCCACCAACAUUCAGCAGAAUUUGCAGCUCCAUGUUUCCAAAGCUUCCAGGGCACUUGCAUUUAGAGAGAGAGAGCAAGCAAGCUGCCUUUCCUCUUCCUCAGUUCUGCCAGCCACACUCUUGCCAUGAUGAGCAGUUUCAGCCAAAAGCUCCUUCCCCUGCCCUAACACCUCCUGCAAGGCCUGAGGUCUGGAAGCCACCUGCGCCUGCUGGCCCCUCCUUUCUUGUUUCUGCAAUGGAUGUUGUGGCCCUGUGAGGGAGAAGAGAAAAAGAAGUUGCCCUCCUCCCUCUAUCCUCACCUCCUGCCAUGCUGUCACCCUUAUAAGAGAGAAGGGCUAACCAUCCAGGCUAAUCCUCCAGUGAUGCAGGAGAGGACAUCCUGGCCGGAAGAGUCAGAGCUUCCAGGUGAGCUCAGGUGGGUCAGCCCCCGAGGCUGUGAAGAGCCCAGGGGCCAGUAGAUGCCACUUUUGCUCCAGGAAGAAUCUUCAACUGUGUCCUUUUUAUUCAAGGGGCUCUCUUUUCAGCGAAUCUCUAGAUGUACUAGUCACAAACACUCGCAUUUAUUAAAAUGUAUCCAUGAUCCCACAAUCCUUUUACAUAUUUCUCUCCAGGAGUAUCACAUUUCUGAGGGCCCUGUGCCUGUUUUCUGCAGGAAGUUGCUGUUGUCCCGGGUCCCCCUGCCCCCAGCACCUCUGUUACAAGAAGCAGACCCUUCAUGCCACACUGGGACCCAGGGAGGCCCCAAGCCAGGAUGCUGGGAUCUUAGUAAAGGUUGGAAUGAUGUCAGAACAUAGAGGAGGCAGAAUUCCCCCCAUAGCAUCAUCCUGGAGGGCGCUGAUUUGUGUGCUCUGCCAGGUUCAUCUGUGACUCAGGAUUUAAAAGCCCCAGGUGUGGUGUCCCUUCUGUGCCUGCAAGGUGCGUCUUUAGCAGUUCUCCCUGGUGUGGAAGGAUCAGUGGUUCUUGCAGCCUAGGCACCCUCCACAGCAAGCCCAACACAGGUGCUGUGAGCAGCUGGUUCAUGAACGGUGAUCCUGGGGAGAAGAGGAGGAUGAAAAUGGAAAACCAGUGCAAAGGUGUGUCAUCCAGUUGGUUACUGCUGUGGGUGCCCGGGCUUCCAUCCCACCAGAGCCCCCACUAGCCAGGGCAGCCUGGCGGAGGUGAGCAUCAUUCUGCUUUCUGGCUGCACCUGUGUGGACAGAGCCCGUUCCAAAGCCUCCCAGGCACAGGGCAGACAUCAAGCAAGGGGCAGAGCUGGGGCGAGGGCUCUGGGUGCCCCCGUUAUUGAACACAGGCCUGAAGGGAGCCUAAGAGGUGGCUGGCAGGAGAUACUACAAGGCAGAAAGACAGGGCAGCAGUCUUUGUACUGUACGUUUUUGUUUUUUAAGAGAGAACAAAAAGUCAAGGUUGAGAGAUGAGAAAUACUCUUGCCAAAAAGAGAACACCAAAAUCCUGGAGUCACGGGUCUUCCAUUACCCUCUCUAGCAUUUCUGCUUGUCUUUUCCCUAGUAUUGGUGAAGAAUUUUUAAAGUAACCAACCCAUACCGUUGGUUACAGGCCCUGUGGUCACCAGGCUGUCUCCCCAUGAUGGGGAUGGAGAGUGGUUAGUGCAGAAACUUAGACCUCCCCUCCAGCUUGUUGAAUGCCCUGAAGUUUAUCUAGAAGGGAAGAUACUCAAGCGUAGGAUUUCAGUGAUGCAUUUGGACAGCAUCAGUACUAUGCUUCAGCGUCAAAAACGUCACUUUGGGUAGGAACAAUACAUAAUGCGUGGCAAUGCCUUUUGUGACACCUGUUCAGGAGAUUCCCAUAGGAAGCUUCUGAGGCAGAGUCCUCAGGUGAGGAGGGGGACAGGCCUGGGUCUUGGGGGAAGGUGGAGAUGACCAGCCUCAUGCCUCUCUCCCCAGUGGCCUCAGUCUCCAUCAGGCAAAUCUUGAGAAGCCUCCUCCAUUCUGCAGGCAAAUGACUGAGAUGUGUGAGCUCUGCUUCCCAACAGGCGGAAAUUCACAUGGGGAAGGGCACCUGUGAAUGGCCUUCUAGAACUAUCAGGAAGUUCUGGAUUUAGUACCCUGUGAGAGCAGAUGGUCCUGGGUGCACUCGGAUGAUCCUGCCUAGCCAGCUGGAUUGCAGAGUGGUCAUCAUUAUCAGUGAGCUAUUGAGGGGUUGAGAGCAGUCAGUGUCAUGUAUAAGGAUGGGUUGGGGUACCGGCCAACGCCCGCCUUGAGGCCUGGCCGCCGGAUGGGAGGCGAGAGCACAAGAGAGUCCUGGCUAGGUGUGCCCCGCUCUGCAGGGCCACACCAUCCACUGGAAACCCUGUGCCCACUGGGCUGCGUGCUAAGAGGCUGUGGCCAAUGCUCUUGUCCAAAUUUUACUGAAUCUGCAGUCUCUCUUAAUUCACUCCAAAGUUUAAUGUGUUAGCUUGCGAAUAAAUAAAUAAAUAAAUAAAUAAAUAAAUAAAUGGAAAGAAACAGUCCUCAGAAAGUCCCAGUCAAAUUUUAAUUCCAACAGAUAUUCAGCAGUUUCCUCUAAGAACAAUGAGAGUUCUGGGGCUAGCCAGUGUUUCUCUUGGAAAAUAAGGAAGAGGGAAAGCGGUGCAUUCAUUUAAAAACCUGCCCUAGGGAGGCAGCGUUCCCUGUGAACUCCGAGGCCACAGUGAGCAGAGCAGGCUGGAGGCCUCCCGGCUGUCCUGCCCCUCCUGCCACAUGCCUGUGAAAAUGCUAGAUAAGGACUUUUUCUCAGCAACUUCCACGCUCCUUCAGUGGGGAUGUCUUUGACUCAGAGCUCUGCCACUGGUUAUCUCCACGAACAGAAAAUGCCACAGAUGGGUUAAUUCACUGUGUUGUUCUCAUUUUCCCUCAGUUUCAGGCUUUUCUCUCCUUGCCUGUUUUCCUCGCUUAAAAAAUGAUGUGGGGGUCCCUAAACGCAUCUACCCCGAUAGAUUUAUGUUUUCUUUUCCAUUAGUCCACUUUGCGUCUCAGCCCUAAAAUUAAGUUUUUGAUUAUAAUGUAAGGAAGUUUUACCAUAUUUUAACUCUGGCUUUUUAAAUACAAAAGAAAAAUAACAGAAUGGCCUUCUAGAACUAUCAGGAACUUCUGGAUCUAGUACCCUGUGGGGACAGAUGGUCUGGAGCCAGCGCACUUGGAUGAUCUCUCUCAGCCAUCUGGACCAUAGAGUGAACUUGUUACUGUCCCUCCAAGGCUGACAACUAUGAGCUCAUACUCUUCUAGCAGUUUAAUUUAGACCCAAGAAAGGCUGUGUGUGUGUGAAUUUGUGAGAGUGUGUGAGUGUGUCUUUGUGCCUGUGUUUCUGUGUGUGUCUGUGUGUACAUGUGUGUCUGUGGGGUGUGUCUGUGUGUGCACGGCUGUGUGUCUGUGCGUGUGCAUGGCUUUGUCUGUGUGUGUGCGCACGCACUCUGCUAAGCUACUCAAUGCAAUUCCUUACUCUUACUUCCCUUUCUGUCACUUCUCCAUAAUUCUUUGUAUUUCGGUUGGGCUGGUAUCUCGCGGCGGCUUCCUCUUUUCCUGCAUUCCUAUAUUUCAUUAUUUGCUCUUGUUCCUCUUCUAGGGCUUUUACAAUAUAGCCAGGAGGAUGUGGAAACCCAGUUACAAGAUGACACACAAGCACAGUGUCACAAUCGCUGUGCUUGGGCCCUACCUCCUGGAGACCAGGGUGGGACGGUGUCUCUGGAUAUGGAGGGAAGGGCGGAAGAUCACGGGGUGGCAGAAGGCCCGACUGUCCGGUCUUCUGGAAGCUGGGGUCUCGUGGUCGCUGGGCUGGUGGUGCUCUAAAACCUAGAGUAACCGAGAGCAGGAUGACUGCACCCCUGACUGCCGACUCACCGGGCUUCGGAGGGCCAUGGGUGUGUGAUUCCACUUGUGAUCCUCCUACUUCCCCAGCCCACCCUGGUGGUCUCCCACUUCUCUCUCUCUGCCUGUGGAGUGUUAUAACCGACUCCUUCUUCUAGGCAUCUCCAUCCCAACCCCAGACCAGUUCCCUUAAACCACCUCCCACCACAGGACCCCCACAAGCAGGGACCUCUCACAGUUCCUGUUGCCUGGGGACUUCAUCUCAGCUUCCAAGGCCUCUGGAACCAGGCCCUGCAUCCUGGGCAUGACUGUCCCCAUGAUUCUCUGAGCCAGCCACCACCCCACCACCCCCCCACCGCCAAGUCCACUGCUGACCCUGCUGUAGCCCCCCACCUCCACUUGUUGAGAUUCCCUCUUCCUGCUUCUCAUUUUGAAUGUCACCCUUCUGUGACUUCUCACAACCCCCCUGCCACCCCUCCCUCCAGUUGGCAUGGCUUAGUCUUCCUAAGAACAUGUGCUGCUUCCCAGUACCCAGGGCUGCUGUGCACCGUGGCACGUGAGUUUCGGUGCAUCUUCCUCCUGCUGUUUAUAAAUUGCAACAUCCCUGGACAGAUCUUGGAUUUUCCCUCUAUAAUUUCUCUGGAGACUCCCUCGGGGUUUGCACACACAUCUGUGGAAUGCCCAAGUUGGAGAUGGUCCUCCCUGAUGUGUAGUGUGGGCUAUUCAGAGGGCCUCAUUUCAUAAACUCAUUAACAGCUAGGACGCGAAGACUUGGAGAAGUUAGCUCAGGACACACGGAGUGGGAGGGAGGCAACGAGUUAAGAAAUGGGCUUUGGAGUGCCUCGAAUUUGGCCUCCACUUUUCUUUUCUACUGUCUUACCUGGUCUUAGGCAGGUCGGGUGACCAUCUGGAGUCGGAGUUUCUCUCAUUUGUAAAGCGGGGGUGAUAUUUUUCUCACAGGGCUGCUUCAAGGGUUAACAAAGUUAAUGUCUAGGAAGGACAUAGCAUAGCACCUUCACCUGGUUGCAAGCCCCUGGAGUCACAUGGCAACAGCUGUGGAACCAGGUAAAUGACUUGACUUACAUGUUACACGCUCUUAGUUGUUCGAUUUGUAAAUGGGAAGAGUGUGUGACCCAAAUUAGUCGUUUCCAGAUAUUUCCUGGUAAAUGGUUGUUGAAUCAUAAAACUAGAAAGAUGGGAAAGAAAGGGAGGAACCCCCCUUACUUCGAAGAAGUGUUGUUGAUGUGAAGGACAGGACUUUUUGAGACACUCUCAUCCUAAGAAACAGCUGAUAUCUACUAGGAAAAAACAUGACAUUUGAAGUUUCUUCCUAAGAGAUGUGAGGUUUUGACAGAAGUGCCAGGAAGCCAGAGGUGUGUGAGUAGUGGGCCAAUCUCGCGUGAAGGCUGUGGGACGGGGCAGGAGAGGGGCAGCCAGCAUUUCCUGAGCGCCAGCUAAUGGCGGGGACCUGGCACCUUUGCUCUGUGACUCUCCAGCUGUAUGGUGACAUGAGGCUGGCGUUUUCUUUGGUUUCAUACGUGAGGAAGCUGAGGCUUGGUGAUGUCCUGUGCAUGGCUCGGACUCCAGAGCUACUCAGAGGCAGAGGCCGUCUGUAAACACCUUCAGGUGGUUGGAGGCAGGGUGCUGCAGCCAAUGCUGAUCACUCACAAGCCAAGGCUUUAUUGUAAGGGCUAAAUAAAAUAACAUAUGCCUAGCAUUUAUACAGCACGGGGCUUUUUAGGAAAUAGUGAGACGACCAUGGAGAGGUGGAGGAAGAGAGAAGGGAAAGAAGAAAAAGAAAAAAAAAGCCUUAAAGAGUUUCUUAAGAGAACUAUAUAUUACAAAGUCCUUGGAGUUUUUUUUCCCUGGUUAGACAUAAGUUUACAUGAAACGUUAAACGGCUUAAAGUAGCCACAUCUCCUUCCUUAUGUCUUCUCACAGCCACUUGUGAGUUUCUUAUCAAGAUACAGAAUUAUGGCCAAGUGCGGUAGCUCACACGUGUAAUCCCAGCACUUUGAGAGACUGAGGUGGAAGGAUCAUGUGUGCUCAGGAGUUUCAGACCAACCUAGGCAAUAUGGUAAAACCCUGUCUCUACAAAAAAAUACAAAAAUUAGCUGGGCAUGGUGGCAUAUUCCAAUAGUUCCAGGCACUCGGGAGGCUGAGACAGGAGGAUUGCUUGAGCCCAAGAGGUCAAGACUGCAGUGAGCUGUGAUCGAGCCACUGCACUACAGCCUGGGCCACAGAGCAAGAUCCUGUCUCAAAAAAUAAAAUAAAAUAAAAUAAAUUCUGCAACAAGUCACAAUUCCUUGCUCAGAAAUCUCUACAGGUGUGCUUCUUUGUUAAGAAAUGGAGGAAACAUGAAUUUCAUCCUGACUUCUGAGUCUUGUAGAGACCAGAUCUGACUCCUGCAGCCUUCUGCCCACAGAGCUGGCAGGCGGGGGAAUGUGCGCAGAGUGAGGAGGAGCUGAUCUGACAUUCCGAACAGUGGAGACUGCUGCCUAUUUGGCCGCACCACUGUCCUUCUGCAUGGAAAAGUCACAGUAAAUAAUGGACUCUCUACCUGUGAGUCGAUUUUACUGAGCUGCCUUUUUAAAUAUAUGUGUAGAAAGGGCGAUCUCUGUGUGUCAUUUGCACAUGUACAUACACAUGUACACACGUGCACACGUGGUCACUCAUGUACACAUGUGUGUGCACCAGUGCACCAGACCAGAUGCACCCACCCAAUUCCACGCUCCUCAGCCCCUUGCUUUCCUCUGCAGACAGCCAGUUCAGCUACAGUUAUGCCAGAUUGCCUGCACUCUGAUCUUUACCAUCACCAGACUCUCAGCUUGAGCUCAUGCCUGAGAAAUCCACUUUCUGGGAGGAAGGCAGAAGAAACUGCCAAGGCAGGACUGAAGACUUGACCUCCACCUGUAGUGGGGUCAGGUCACCAGAGGCUGGCUGACUCCCCAGGAUUUCUCAGCAGAGUAUUACACAAAUACCCCUUCCUUAAAGAUUAGCAACCACUUAAAGACACAAAGUGUGCAGGACUGUACCCAUGGCCGAGAGCGGCGGGAUUAAGAGGGCAACUGAGUUGUUCUUCCCAUCCCUCCUCCUCUGUGCUGAGUCACCUUCUGCUUGGAAUUCUGACAGGGACCCGUUGGGCUUCUGGAAGGGAGGGACAGCAGAGGAUCCACCCUCUGUGUGUCCUGGGGGAGAUUACUUAUCUCUGGCCUCCCUGAAGCAGGGCCUGGGCUUCUGGAAUCUUUGAGGCUGACACCCUGCCAGCCCUGGGGAUGAGAGGGAAUGGCCGUGUCUGUCUGCAGAGCCUGAGGAGGAGCUGAGCACAGCCUCCAGAGUUCUCUUCAGUUGAUCGCUUAGGUGGACAAAGGCCACAGAAAUGGAUUUAAACUCCUCAGCCCUUUCUUUGCAUGUUUGUUCUCAUUUGAAGUCAGAAGUGAUAUGUCCUACACCUCAAGAACGUGUGAAAUGCACAUACAAUAACCCCAUUUCAGGAAGCCAAGUCCAGCUUAACAGUCAAAACAUUUCCUUCAGUCUUUAGUCCUUCACUUUGCCGAACUCCCUUUUACACCGGCAGCAACAGUUUAACCUGUUGCUUCUGUAAGAGUGUGCUACUGGGAAAACCACAUCUAAAACACGUGUGCAGUUACAUCAGCUAGAGCACAUGCUAAACAGUUGAUCAAAGGCUCUUGCCUUGUGGCCCACGCUGCAGACACUCUGACGACUGCCGAGCUCCGCAGCCCCAUGUCGUCCCUUCCGCACUGCCUGCUGUGCCUCUCCUCUCCAUGUGGCAGGGAACACAGCCAGUCAUCACCAUGUGGCUCUGCCCGGCGCUGCCCCAGCAUGUCCUGACAGGGCCUAGAUAUGGAAAGGUGGCUCUCCAUGCACACACCCCAAGCCCCUCCUGCCCGCCGUGUGACCCACACUCUUAUGGGCAGCCCAGUUAUUUUGUAGCAUUUCCCUUCCUUAUCAUUUUGGCCCAGUGAUCCAGCACAAAUCUCCCUUAUUAGAAUAAAAUUUGGAAUGACAAAAUUAAAUUUCAUUUUUCACUUAUAUUGAGGACCUCACACUCUUCACCCCUGCCACGAUCCCUGACAAGAGCCUUCCUAUCUAAUCAUUGUUCCUCCAGCCCUCUUAGUUUUCUUCAGCCUUUCUUGAUUGCCUGAAUGUCCCUUUCCCUUCUCCUUUUAAAGCAUGAACCAAGCUUUCUUACCCCGUUCUCAUUAUCAUUUUUGCAUUUUCUUCUUUGCAUAUGAUUCUCCUUAAAUUAUAAAACUUGGGGGUAAUUUCUAGAGGUGCCAUCAUAGUGCUUCUGUCUACUCAGUGUCUUUAGAAUCAGCAAAUAUCAUUUUUACAAAAAAGUAGUAUUUCUUCCAAAAAAGAGUAAGCAAGAAGGUUACAACACUGGGAAAAUAUCCCUAAGCCUGUUCUUCAACCUGUUGAAUGUUUUCCCCUAAAUUGUUAUAUGGAGAUCCUGGACCCGGAAGUUGGCUGACAUGAAACAGGCCUAGCAGGGCAGCUGAGGAAAUGCUCCAACCUCAGGAUCCAGGAAGAUUGCACAUGGCACCAAAACAAUCAUUUAAAAGCUAAUCCUGGCCAGGCACAGUGGCUCACGCCUGUAAUCCCAGCACUUUGGGAGGCCGAGGUGGGCUGAUCACAAGGUCAAGAGAUCGAGACCAUCCUGACCAACAUGGUGAAACCCCAUCUCUACCAAAAGUACAAAUAUUAGCUGGGCAUGGUGGUGCGCGCCUGUAGUCCCAGCUACCCGGGAGGCUGAGGCAGGAGAAUCACUUGAACCCGGGAGGAGGAGGUUGCAGUGAGCCAAGAUCAUGCCACUGCACUCCAGCCUGGUGACAGAGCAAGACUCCAUCUCAAAAAAGAAAAAAAAAGCUAAUCCCAUAAAAGAACCAUCAUUUUGAACCUGCUGUUUCCUUUCUUGUACUCUUUAGAAGUACCCAUUUCUCCCUUUCUAAGCCAUAGGUGUAUUAAUUGGAGCUUUUUCUAUCUUAAUUAGUUCACUGUGAACAAUUAAAAUUGUGUUAAUAAAACAAAAACAAAAAUAGGACUGGUGCCUAGUUGUACUACAUGAAGAGAGAAAGGGCCAGACAUUGGUUUUUCCUAAUCUUCUGUCAAGUUCUCCAAAUCAUCUGCUCUGGAAGGUAGCUCCAACAGCUGGGAUUUGAAGUAAAGCAUAGUGACUUUGGCCAUCACUGACAUGUCCCAUUUGAAGCAACCAAAACUGUCCCUCGACCUGACACUCAUCCCUGAAACACCAUGAGGGUAAGUGAGGCGCUUCGGAAGGUCCACUCAACCCCAUUGCCAGAUAGAGUAAGUGUCUGCCAGGGGCAUUUGGAGCUGAAGGGAAGACUGUACAGACUCACGGUUUGCAGGCACUGAAGGCGUUUUCCUGCCUUCUUUUUCACCUUCAGUGGACUUGCAAAGCACUAGCCCUAUUGUUUUUCCCAUCUGGGAAACAUGGUGAAUGUUGGUUGGUUGUAGCUAAUCCUAUGGGUCUUGAGGUCUUUGUUGACAAGAAGGUAGAUGUUAUCUUUAUCUGCGUGUGGCUUUCUACUAAAACAUGAGCUACAGGGCUCUCUUUUUUGUUUUAAAGCAUUUUUCCAUAAGGUUCACCCUUACUAUUGCUUAUCUGAAUAAUAUUACCUGCUGAGAAGUUUAUUCAUUGCUCACCAGUUGUAGGGAGAUUUUGACACAGGACUGGAGGAUUUUUUUCUCAUCGUAACAGUGCAGACCCAUGGAAAGCUUGGAAGCAGUUGUGACCGGAUAAGAGCAGGUUGAGGAUGAUAAUCUUAGGGCAAUGAGCAGGUUGAUUGAGAGGGGUGCCUGAAAGCAAGGUCCCCAUGAUGCAAGCAAACAAACUCACAUGCCAGACGGUGGACAGGAAACACAGGCAGGAUGUGGUGCAGGCUGGGCUGCCUUGGCUGGGCAAAGGCAGGGGCUUCAUGGCCAUGCUGGGAUGUGACGUGGUUGGAAAACAAUAAGAAUGGAGACCUCUCCAAAGACCUCAGACAUAAUUUGGCCAUGAGAGGCAAGGGUAGAGGCGAGCCCCCUGUGGGUUGGAAUGUAUGGAAUCCAGAUGAAGCACCAUCAACAUGCAUGGGCUACAUAGGAGAGCUGGGUCUGGGGGAAAAGAUGGGAUUUGGGUUUGGGUGUGCAUGUUCCAGGCAUGGAGGGAAGAAUGGGCAGAAUGACGAGGAUCAAGCCCUGGUGGAGCCCCCAGACCAGGGCCCUGGGCAUAUUUCCACUUGCCUUCUUCUGCAAACUUUUGUGUGCCUGUUGGGUGGAAGGUACUAUGCUGGGGCCAUCCAGGAUCCGGAGCAGUGUAAGACAUCAUGGCCUGCAUGGUGUGACCCUUGACAUCUGAAAAGAACGAGCUGGUGGAGUGGGAAGGAGACAAGUGGCAGCAGAGUUGACAUCAUCAGGACUGACUGCAGGACAGGCGGUGAAACGAGCCACUGAGGAGUUACCCAGUGCCCUGGGGAGCUUAGAUGUGAGACUUACACCACCCAGCACUCCCCAGCUCUGUGUCCCUGGGUCCCACUGAACUUGAUUGUAUUUUAGUUGCCUCUUUUCUAAGACCGGAGCAACAAUACCUUCCUUGAGUGUGCAUGUGCAGUCCAUAGAUGGCAGCCAGUGUUCUCUUCCCAUGAGAAGACUCUGAGCCUCCUCACUAGAGGGUGGUCUAAAAACAAAUGGAUCCAUCCACAGAAGGUCUGAAAGGUUUUCAUAGAAUCUUGACUUGGUAGCACUUCAGGAUCUAACUCGUGCUUUCCAGAAGUGUGGCCUGUGGUGUUCUGUCUGGAGUAUUUGGUCCUCCCAUCCACCUCCACCUUGCUGUCCUGUCCUGUGACUCUCACUAGCUCAGUCACCGGGUCAGGAAGCCCUGCCAUGAAAUGCUAGAUUUGGAGGCAUUGCCAAGGUACCACAAACCAUACUCAAACAAGGUCAUAAUAGACUAGUGAUCUCACUGUGGCUAACAGGUUCAUGUGAUUUAAAGAAUGACAGCAUUUUUUCUAAAUUUUAUAAAUUUUAUAAAUUUCUCCUAAAUACAAAUCUGAAUGUGUUUACCUUUAGACAGAUUUUCCCAGAAAAUUGUCAGUGUUCUCGAAUUUGAAAGUAGAUCAGAUCUCCUCCCUCUAGUUUUGAAAAUCUCAAGUAGGUUUAGCCUCUCCCCAGAGUGACAACGGCACAAGAAGUUUAUAAUUUUAUGCACAGCUAAAUGCAAACUGAAAAGUGUGGUUUGUGGGUAUUUCAUUUUUCCCAUAAUGUUCAUCAAUUUGGCAAUUCAAAUAGGAUUCAGAAUCCAAGGUGUUCGCAGCAUUUUAUAUGAAAAUGUGCCUGAGAGUUUGGGGAAUAGAAAUUCUUACCAAAUAAGUUAAAUUUGCUCUUGAUAAGAAUAUAUUUUGUAAAAUGUAGAAAACUGAGAAAAAAAGUUUGACACCUGUUUUAUCUGCAUCCUUUUAUUAAACAGUGGCCUGAAUUUACUAAAGGACAGAGAACAGGGUUGAGAGGUAAUCACUGAAUAAUAGCUUCGCUAAUCCCACAGUGACUGCUUCUUAUGACAAGCAAGAGGGUCAACUUAGAGGCAGGACUGUCUUCAGGGGCAAAAGCAAGUCAGCACCUACAAACCUCUCCAAGAGAGUGAGAAAAAGCAGGUUGUAUGGCUCAUUUUGCAGCUUGCCAGAAGCAAUGUGGGAAUAUUGUCAGACUGCACAGACCUGGGGCCAGCUGGCUCCUAGAGUGCGAGGAGCUCUCAGUGACUGCUGUGCAUACUCACCUGCUCUGUGACUUUGUUCAGUCCCUACCCUGGAUGUGUGGUGAAGGGUGCCAGGCUUAGCUGCUGGACCAGUGAGGUCCCUGAGGGGGCAGGGCUAAGAGGUGUAGCAGUCGCACUUGACCAGUCAUUGAUUCACUGGUUGGGAAUUUGUUCAUUGAGGGGACACCAUUACUCCCCAUGCCUCACGUGCAGGUGAGUGUGUGUAUAUUUGCAUUAACACACAAACACACUUAUGUGUGUCCCUGUAUGUGCAGCUGCAGUACCUUACACAUCUUCCAGUGCCUCUCAAGCAUCAUAAAAACAGCUUCCACAAAACCUCUACUACCCACCUGGCAUCCACAGAGCUCCCAGUGAUUGGCUCCCAAAAGAUACUGAACUUUGGCAUGGAACAGAGUGAGUUUCCACAUUUGCUGUUGUACAUAAUUACCUGUCCAGCUAGAAUAGUACACACUUCUUUUACUGAGCCCAGAAGUUUAUGUGCCUGAACACGGAUGGUACAGGAACAAGGGUGAGCGCUUAUCAAUUCAGCAUUACUCUGGAGACAUGAAACAAACUAAUAGGUACAGCUAUAUUUUGUUUUUUAAACAAUUUUGUGAACCACAUAUUUGGGACAAAAAUCAACAAGUAAAUUUGAAUUACACUAGGCAAAGGACUGAUUCUUUUGAAACGUGAUUGACAUUCAACGUCUAACUUUCCAAAAGAAGACAUACAUGUGGCCCACAAUCAUAUGAAAUAAAGUUCAUCAUCAUUGAUCAUUAGAGAAAUGCAAAUCAAAACCACAAUGAGAUACCAUCUCACACCAGUCAGAAUGGUUAUUAAUAAAAAGUCAAAGAAUGACAGUUGCUGGUGAGGUUGUAGAGAAAAAGGAACGCUUAUACACUGUUGAGGGGAUUGUAAAUUAGUUCAACCAUGUGGAAGACAGUGUGGCAAUUCCUCAAAGACCUAUAUACCAUUUGACCCAGCAAUCCCAUUACUGCAUAUAUACCCAAAGGAAUAUGAGUCAUUCUACCGUAAGACACAUGCACGCAUUUGUUUGUUGCAGCACUAUUCACGAUAGCAAAAACAUGGAAUCAACCUACAUGCCCAUCAAUGAUAGACUGGAUAAAGAAAAUGUGGUACAUAUACCCCAUGGAAUACUAUGCAGCCAUAAGAAAAAGAAUGAGAUCAUGCCCUUUGCAGGAACAUGGAUGGAGCUGGAGGCCAUUAUCCUUAGCAAACUAACCCAGGAACAGAAAACCAAGUGCAGAUGUUCUCACUUUUAAGUGUGAGCUGAAUGAGGAGAAUACAUGGGCACAUAGAGGGGCCUAUCAGAGGGUGGAGGGUGGGAGAAGGAAGAGUAUCAGAAAAAAUAACAGGUAGUAGAUUUAAUACCGGAUGACAAAACAAUCUGUAUAACAAACCCCCAUGACAUGAGUUUACCUAUAUAACAAACCCGCACAUGUACUCCUGAACUUAAAAGUUAAAUUAAAAAAAAAUUAAUGUCUAAUAAUAUAUUACAGUAUUCUUCAUAUUCAAUGGCAAUGUGUGAAGUGGGAAGUGUCUUGACAGAAUUCGGUGUUUCAAGGCUUACACUUUGAUGCCCAAGACUGCACAAGGCUACAUUUUCUACUGUUACAUAUGGGGCUGAUGACUUUAGGGAUUUCCAUGCAAUAAUUCCCAAAUCUUUCUCUCCCAGUAAUGUUAAAGUAGAGACUCAGAGUGAUGAAGAGAAUGGGCGUGCCUGUGAAAUGAAUGGGGAAGAAUGUGCGGAGGAUUUACGAAUGCUUGAUGCCUCGGGAGAGAAAAUGAAUGGCUCCCACAGGGACCAAGGCAGCUCGGCUUUGUCGGGAGUUGGAGGCAUUCGACUUCCUAACGGAAAACUAAAGUGUGAUAUCUGUGGGAUCAUUUGCAUCGGGCCCAAUGUGCUCAUGGUUCACAAAAGAAGCCACACUGGAGAACGGCCCUUCCAGUGCAAUCAGUGCGGGGCCUCAUUCACCCAGAAGGGCAACCUGCUCCGGCACAUCAAGCUGCAUUCCGGGGAGAAGCCCUUCAAAUGCCACCUCUGCAACUACGCCUGCCGCCGGAGGGACGCCCUCACUGGCCACCUGAGGACGCACUCCGUUGGUAAACCUCACAAAUGUGGAUAUUGUGGCCGAAGCUAUAAACAGCGAAGCUCUUUAGAGGAACAUAAAGAGCGCUGCCACAACUACUUGGAAAGCAUGGGCCUUCCGGGCACACUGUACCCAGUCAUUAAAGAAGAAACUAAUCACAGUGAAAUGGCAGAAGACCUGUGCAAGAUAGGAUCAGAGAGAUCUCUCGUGCUGGACAGACUAGCAAGUAACGUCGCCAAACGUAAGAGCUCUAUGCCUCAGAAAUUUCUUGGGGACAAGGGCCUGUCCGACACGCCCUACGACAGCAGCGCCAGCUACGAGAAGGAGAACGAAAUGAUGAAGUCCCACGUGAUGGACCAAGCCAUCAACAACGCCAUCAACUACCUGGGGGCCGAGUCCCUGCGCCCGCUGGUGCAGACGCCCCCGGGCGGUUCCGAGGUGGUCCCGGUCAUCAGCCCGAUGUACCAGCUGCACAAGCCGCUCGCGGAGGGCACCCCGCGCUCCAACCACUCGGCCCAGGACAGCGCCGUGGAGAACCUGCUGCUGCUCUCCAAGGCCAAGUUGGUGCCCUCGGAGCGCGAGGCGUCCCCGAGCAACAGCUGCCAAGACUCCACGGACACCGAGAGCAACAACGAGGAGCAGCGCAGCGGUCUCAUCUACCUGACCAACCACAUCGCCCCGCACGCGCGCAACGGGCUGUCGCUCAAGGAGGAGCACCGCGCCUACGACCUGCUGCGCGCCGCCUCCGAGAACUCGCAGGACGCGCUCCGCGUGGUCAGCACCAGCGGGGAGCAGAUGAAGGUGUACAAGUGCGAACACUGCCGGGUGCUCUUCCUGGAUCACGUCAUGUACACCAUCCACAUGGGCUGCCACGGCUUCCGUGAUCCUUUUGAGUGCAACAUGUGCGGCUACCACAGCCAGGACCGGUACGAGUUCUCGUCGCACAUAACGCGAGGGGAGCACCGCUUCCACAUGAGCUAAAGCCCUCCCGCGCCCCCACCCCAGACCCCGAGCCACCCCAGGAAAAGCACAAGGACUGCCGCCUUCUCGCUCCCGCCAGCAGCAUAGACUGGACUGGACCAGACAAUGUUGUGUUUGGAUUUGUAACUGUUUUUUGUUUUUUGUUUGAGUUGGUUGAUUGGGGUUUGAUUUGCUUUUGAAAAGAUUUUUAUUUUUAGAGGCAGGGCUGCAUUGGGAGCAUCCAGAACUGCUACCUUCCUAGAUGUUUCCCCAGACCGCUGGCUGAGAUUCCCUCACCUGUCGCUUCCUAGAAUCCCCUUCUCCAAACGAUUAGUCUAAAUUUUCAGAGAGAAAUAGAUAAAACACGCCACAGCCUGGGAAGGAGCGUGCUCUACCCUGUGCUAAGCACGGGGUUCGCGCACCAGGUGUCUUUUUCCAGUCCCCAGAAGCAGAGAGCACAGCCCCUGCUGUGUGGGUCUGCAGGUGAGCAGACAGGACAGGUGUGCCGCCACCCAAGUGCCAAGACACAGCAGGGCCAACAACCUGUGCCCAGGCCAGCUUCGAGCUACAUGCAUCUAGGGCGGAGAGGCUGCACUUGUGAGAGAAAAUACUAUUUCAAGUCAUAUUCUGCGUAGGAAAAUGAAUUGGUUGGGGAAAGUCGUGUCUGUCAGACUGCCCUGGGUGGAGGGAGACGCCGGGCUAGAGCCUUUGGGAUCGUCCUGGAUUCACUGGCUUUGCGGAGGCUGCUCAGAUGGCCUGAGCCUCCCGAGGCUUGCUGCCCCGUAGGAGGAGACUGUCUUCCCGUGGGCAUAUCUGGGGAGCCCUGUUCCCCGCUUUUUCACUCCCAUACCUUUAAUGGCCCCCAAAAUCUGUCACUACAAUUUAAACACCAGUCCCGAAAUUUGGAUCUUCUUUCUUUUUGAAUCUCUCAAACGGCAACAUUCCUCAGAAACCAAAGCUUUAUUUCAAAUCUCUUCCUUCCCUGGCUGGUUCCAUCUAGUACCAGAGGCCUCUUUUCCUGAAGAAAUCCAAUCCUAGCCCUCAUUUUAAUUAUGUACAUCUGUUUGUAGCCACAAGCCUGAAUUUCUCAGUGUUGGUAAGUUUCUUUACCUACCCUCACUAUAUAUUAUUCUCGUUUUAAAACCCAUAAAGGAGUGAUUUAGAACAGUCAUUAAUUUUCAACUCAAUGAAAUAUGUGAAGCCCAGCAUCUCUGUUGCUAACACACAGAGCUCACCUGUUUGAAACCAAGCUUUCAAACAUGUUGAAGCUCUUUACUGUAAAGGCAAGCCAGCAUGUGUGUCCACACAUACAUAGGAUGGCUGGCUCUGCACCUGUAGGAUAUUGGAAUGCACAGGGCAAUUGAGGGACUGAGCCAGACCUUCGGAGAGUAAUGCCACCAGAUCCCCUAGGAAAGAGGAGGCAAAUGGCACUGCAGGUGAGAACCCCGCCCAUCCGUGCUAUGACAUGGAGGCACUGAAGCCCGAGGAAGGUGUGUGGAGAUUCUAAUCCCAACAAGCAAGGGUCUCCUUCAAGAUUAAUGCUAUCAAUCAUUAAGGUCAUUACUCUCAACCACCUAGGCAAUGAAGAAUAUACCAUUUCAAAUAUUUACAGUACUUGUCUUCACCAACACUGUCCCAAGGUGAAAUGAAGCAACAGAGAGGAAAUUGUACAUAAGUACCUCAGCAUUUAAUCCAAACAGGGGUUCUUAGUCUCAGCACUAUGACAUUUUGGGCUGACUACUUAUUUGUUAGGCGGGAGCUCUCCUGUGCAUUGUAGGAUAAUUAGCAGUAUCCCUGGUGGCUACCCAAUAGACGCCAGUAGCACCCCGAAUUGACAACCCAAACUCUCCAGACAUCACCAACUGUCCCCUGCGAGGAGAAAUCACUCCUGGGGGAGAACCACUGACCCAAAUGAAUUCUAAACCAAUCAAAUGUCUGGGAAGCCCUCCAAGAAAAAAAAUAGAAAAGCACUUGAAGAAUAUUCCCAAUAUUCCCGGUCAGCAGUAUCAAGGCUGACUUGUGUUCAUGUGGAGUCAUUAUAAAUUCUAUAAAUCAAUUAUUCCCCUUCGGUCUUAAAAAUAUAUUUCCUCAUAAACAUUUGAGUUUUGUUGAAAAGAUGGAGUUUACAAAGAUACCAUUCUUGAGUCAUGGAUUUCUCUGCUCACAGAAGGGUGUGGCAUUUGGAAACGGGAAUAAACAAAAUUGCUGCACCAAUGCACUGAGUGAAGGAAGAGAGACAGAGGAUCAAGGGCUUUAGACAGCACUCCUUCAAUAUGCAAUCACAGAGAAAGAUGCGCCUUAUCCAAGUUAAUAUCUCUAAGGUGAGAGCCUUCUUAGAGUCAGUUUGUUGCAAAUUUCACCUACUCUGUUCUUUUCCAUCCAUCCCCCUGAGUCAGUUGGUUGAAGGGAGUUAUUUUUUCAAGUGGAAUUCAAACAAAGCUCAAACCAGAACUGUAAAUAGUGAUUGCAGGAAUUCUUUUCUAAACUGCUUUGCCCUUUCCUCUCACUGCCUUUUAUAGCCAAUAUAAAUGUCUCUUUGCACACCUUUUGUUGUGGUUUUAUAUUGUAACACCAUUUUUCUUUGAAACUAUUGUAUUUAAAGUAAGGUUUCAUAUUAUGUCAGCAAGUAAUUAACUUAUGUUUAAAAGGUGGCCAUAUCAUGUACCAAAAGUUGCUGAAGUUUCUCUUCUAGCUGGUAAAGUAGGAGUUUGCAUGACUUCACACUUUUUUUGCGUAGUUUCUUCUGUUGUAUGAUGGCGUGAGUGUGUGUCUUGGGUACCGCUGUGUACUACUGUGUGCCUAGAUUCCAUGCACUCUCGUUGUGUUUGAAGUAAAUAUUGGAGACCGGAGGGUAACAGGUUGGCCUGUUGAUUACAGCUAGUAAUCGCUGUGUCUUGUUCCGCCCCCUCCCUGACACCCCAGCUUCCCAGGAUGUGGAAAGCCUGGAUCUCAGCUCCUUGCCCCAUAUCCCUUCUGUAAUUUGUACCUAAAGAGUGUGAUUAUCCUAAUUCAAGAGUCACUAAAACUCAUCACAUUAUCAUUGCAUAUCAGCAAAGGGUAAAGUCCUAGCACCAAUUGCUUCACAUACCAGCAUGUUCCAUUUCCAAUUUAGAAUUAGCCACAUAAUAAAAUCUUAGAAUCUUCCUUGAGAAAGAGCUGCCUGAGAUGUAGUUUUGUUAUAUGGUUCCCCACCGACCAUUUUUGUGCUUUUUUCUUGUUUUGUUUUGUUUUGACUGCACUGUGAGUUUUGUAGUGUCCUCUUCUUGCCAAAACAAACGCGAGAUGAACUGGACUUAUGUAGACAAAUCGUGAUGCCAGUGUAUCCUUCCUUUCUUCAGUUCCAGCAAUAAUGAAUGGUCAACUUUUUUAAAAUCUAGAUCUCUCUCAUUCAUUUCAAUGUAUUUUUACUUUAAGAUGAACCAAAAUUAUUAGACUUAUUUAAGAUGUACAGGCAUCAGAAAAAAGAAGCACAUAAUGCUUUUGGUGCGAUGGCACUCACUGUGAACAUGUGUAACCACAUAUUAAUAUGCAAUAUUGUUUCCAAUACUUUCUAAUACAGUUUUUUAUAAUGUUGUGUGUGGUGAUUGUUCAGGUCGAAUCUGUUGUAUCCAGUACAGCUUUAGGUCUUCAGCUGCCCUUCUGGCGAGUACAUGCACAGGAUUGUAAAUGAGAAAUGCAGUCAUAUUUCCAGUCUGCCUCUAUGAUGAUGUUAAAUUAUUGCUGUUUAGCUGUGAACAAGGGAUGUACCACUGGAGGAAUAGAGUAUCCUUUUGUACACAUUUUGAAAUGCUUCUUCUGUAGUGAUAGAACAAAUAAAUGCAACGAAUACUCUGUCUGCCCUAUCCCGUGAAGUCCACACUGGCGUAAGAGAAGGCCCAGCAGAGCAGGAAUCUGCCUAGACUUUCUCCCAAUGAGAUCCCAAUAUGAGAGGGAGAAGAGAUGGGCCUCAGGACAGCUGCAAUACCACUUGGGAACACAUGUGGUGUCUUGAUGUGGCCAGCGCAGCAGUUCAGCACAACGUACCUCCCAUCUACAACAGUGCUGGACGUGGGAAUUCUAAGUCCCAGUCUUGAGGGUGGGUGGAGAUGGAGGGCAACAAGAGAUACAUUUCCAGUUCUCCACUGCAGCAUGCUUCAGUCAUUCUGUGAGUGGCCGGGCCCAGGGCCCUCACAAUUUCACUACCUUGUCUUUUACAUAGUCAUAAGAAUUAUCCUCAACAUAGCCUUUUGACGCUGUAAAUCUUGAGUAUUCAUUUACCCUUUUCUGAUCUCCUGGAAACAGCUGCCUGCCUGCAUUGCACUUCUCUUCCCGAGGAGUGGGGUAAAUUUAAAAGUCAAGUUAUAGUUUGGAUGUUAGUAUAGAAUUUUGAAAUUGGGAAUUAAAAAUCAGGACUGGGGACUGGGAGACCAAAAAUUUCUGAUCCCAUUUCUGAUGGAUGUGUCACACCUUUUCUGUCAAAAUAAAAUGUCUUGGAGGUUAUGACUCCUUGGUGAAA